AUGGACAGCAUGCUGUAUUAGCUUCCUAGGAAAGGGUGCAUCAGAGGUGAUUUUCAAAAAUCUUAUAUGUCUGAACAUAUUUUCAUUUACAUUACAUGGCUAAUUGAUAGUUUGAUGAGGAAUAGAAAUCUAAGUUGAAAAUAAUUUUACCUCAGAAUUUUGAAGGCAUCAUUUUAUUGUCUUCCAUUUUCUAGUGUUGCUUUUGUGUAUAAUAGUCAGUGCCACUGUCAUUCCUUAUCUACAUGGGUGACCUCUCUUCCUCUCCCUCCCAAUCUGGUUGUUAAGAUCUUUUCUAUUCUGUUCUGAAAUAUACAGUCAUGUCCUGUAGUAUAUAUAUUUUUUCAUAAAUGAUACCGUGCACUCAGAGGGUUCUUUCAGUCAAAGUUCAUGUCCUCCUGUUCUGGGAAAUUGUUUUAUGCUAGUUCUUAGAUAAUUUCUUCCCUCAGUUUUUUUCUAGUCUCUUUUCAGAACAACUAAUUAGUUGGAUUUUGGGUCUCUUGAACUAAUCCUUUCAUUUCCUCUCGUUUUCUCUUGUGUUUCCAUCUGCCUCCAGCUUCUACUUUUAGUGAGAUUUCCUGACUUAGAAUCUGUCUUCAUCACUGACUAGUGCUUGAGUAUGUUACUUAAUGUCUUUUGCUAGUUUCUCCAACUGUAGGAUUAAUUAUUGAACUCAUUUUAGAGGAUUAUUGUGAGAAUUAAAUGACUUACUGCAUGUAAAGCAUAGCACAUAGAAAGUAAUACAUUGUGGCAGAUGGCUUUCAGCUCUGGCUGUUAUUGCUUCUUCAAUUUUAUUUUCAUUUUUGAUAUCUUAUUUUUAAUUUUGGGAACUCUUUCUCCCUCUAUUUUUAUAGCAACUUUUUCUUCAUGGGUACAGUAGCUUGUUGUAAUUCUCUUUGAGUGUUAAUUGCAGUUUUUUAUUCUGUUUAGUUUUCUUCUUUCUUACAUAGUUGCUUUUAUCCAAAUUCAUUUUUGUUUCUUUUAGUUCCUUUCUUUCCUAUGGAAGCUUUCCUCAAAUGGCUAAUGAUCCUCAUUGUUGGUCCAUAUUUAAGAGUAAUGUAGCCGGGCAAAAUGGCUCAUGCAUAUAAUCCUAGCACUUUGGGAGGCCGAGGCGGGCGGAUUGCCUGAACUCAGGAGUUCAAAACCAGCCUGGGCAACAUGGCGAAACCCCGUCUCUACUAAAAUACAAAAUAUUAGCUGGGCAUGGUGGUGUGUGCCUGUAGUCCCAGCUACUCAGAAGGCUGAGGCACAAGAAUUGCUUGAACCCGGGAGGCUGAGAUUGUACCACUGCACUCCAGCCUGAGUGACAGAGUGAGACUCUGCCUCAAAAAAAAAAAAAAAGAAGAAGAAGAAGAAGAACAGACUUCAGCUCAGCUGCAGGGAAAUAUGAUCAUGCCAUUGCACUACAGCCUGGGUGACACAAGAAAUAAAAAUAUUAAAAAAAAAGAAUGAAGGACUUAAAACUGAAAACAAAAACCCCAAAAAAGUGUUUUUGUACAUGUGUAAGCCUCAUCAGCUAGCUUGAUUUUACUGUGGAUUGAUUGGAUAAGCACCCACACCGUAAGCUUCAGUACAAAUGUUCCUUAACUUGCAGUGGGGUUGUGCCCCAAUAAACUCAUUAUAGCUUGAAAAUCUGUUGAAUGCACCUAACCUACAGAACCUCAUAGCUUAGUCGAACAUACCUUAAACAUGCUCAGAACACUUAUAUUAGCCUACAGUUGGGCAAAAUCAUGUAACACAAAGCCUAUUUUAUAAUAAACUUGAAUAUCUCAUGUAGCAUGCUAGUAUUAAAUACUGUUCUGAAAGUCAAAAACAGAAUGGUCAUCUAGGUAUUUAAAGCACUGUUUCUACUGAAUGUGUAUUGCUUUUGUACCAUCAUAAAGUAAGUUGAACCAUUGUAAGUUGAGGACUGUUCGUCCAUAGGUUUCCUUUCUGGAAACCUAUUCAGUUUUUUCCAGCAAAAAUUCUUCAGUUUCCUAUCUGCAGGGUACCACAUGUCUUGUUGCCAGUCUUUUUGUCCUUGCUUGUUUUAAAACUAUGGCACAGGGGAUAGGGUUGGCAGCAUGGGGGUUGGAGGUUCACUUUGCAAUACCGAUACUUUCACUUGGUUUACUUCUGUGAAAACCGAAGAACAGGGCCGCCCUCCUUCAUAUGAAGAUGUGUUUGAUGUCUCAGGGUCUGGGACCUCUUUGGUUCACUCUUUGGUUCAAGUUAUCCACAGACUAUACCUCCUUUUUUCUGCAGUGAUAUGAGAGGUGGUGGUGAUGGUGAGUUUACCUGGCUGUACCACAUUCAACCAGUCCUCUGGUUUAGGGCCUGCUUCUCAACCCAGGUUUCUGUGGGACCAGGGGCUGAGCCUUUCCAAGGUUCUGGGGUGAAAAUUAGCUUGCUUCUCAUUAAUAUCCCCCCAUAGUCAUUUGGGGCUUUGUCCAUUUUCCUAAAUUAGUUUCCACUUCAUCAUCUGCUUUCUGUCCUCCAAAAGUAUGUCAGCAUCUGUGAUCCACUAUAUCUCCUUGACUAUUCUUUUUGUCUUUGUGGGUUUGUACAUUUUUGUUUUUGUUCCUUUACUCAUUGUUUAAGGUGGCUUGGUAAAGGGAUAGAGAUAAAUGCGUGAGUAUUUUCUGUACUUAACUGGAAUUCAGGGAAAGUAUUACUAUUAGUAAACCAAAUUGAAAUUGUUCAUUGAUGGACUGCAAGGUAUUCCAGAAAUAUUUCAUUAAUGUAUCCAUUCAGCAACUGUUUAAGGAGUGCUUACUGUGUACUAGGCAUUGUUAUAGUUUUCAAGAUAAAUAUUCUGUUCGCAUGAAGCUUUUAUUCUAUCAGGAAACAGACAAUAAACAGCUAAACAAAAAUAAAAUGUGAAGAGAGCAGUAAAUGCUAUAAAGAAAAGGGAAGGGAUCAAAAGUGACAGGAAUUACUGUCUAAGCACAUUCAGGGAGAUUUUUUUCUGAGGGCAACAUUUAAACAGAAACCUGAAUGAAGUGAGAGAAUUAUUUGCGUGAGUGUCUGGGGGUUGGGGGUUACAGAGGUGGGGAACACUCCAGACAGGGAAGAAGUGGAGGAGCAUGCUUGGUACAAUAAAGGAAUAAUGAAGAGUCCUGUGUGGCAGCAGUGCAGGGAGGGAGGGAGGAAGAAGGUCAUAGGAGAUGAGGUCAGAGUGGGAGGUGCGGCCAGAUCAUUCUGGGUAUUAUAGGCCAUGGUCAAGAGUUUGUAUUUUAUUUCACAUAAAAUAUAUUUUGGGGAGGUAUUGGAGAGUUUUCAGCAAGAGAAUGACCUAUCUUUGGGGGUUGAAUCACAAGCCUACCGAUAAUGUAAACUGCCACAGUCAGUUCCUGCCCUGACAGACCAAGCUCUCUUCCUUGAUGGUGGGCAAAUUUGGGGUUGCUCCCUAUUUUAAAACCAUUGCCACCCGUAGUCCCCACUGUAGAAUUUCCUUAGGUGGCCAUAUUAUAUACUACGUGAACUCUGGCUUCCUUGGUUUUAUACCUCAUGGGCUGAGUUGUUAAGAUUCCUACUCUUUUCCGGCAUUGGGGUUGGGGGUGUUAGGGAACAGGGUCUCACUCUGUCACCUAGGCUGAAGAGCAGAGGUGUGAUCACAGCUCACUGUAACCUUGAACUGCUGGGCUCAAGCAGUCCUCCCGCCUCAGCCUUCCAAGGAGCUAGGAUUACAGGUGUGCACCAUGACCCAGCUAAUUAAAAAAAAAAAAAAAAUGUUUUUUUGGUAGAGACAGGAACUCACUAUGUUGUACAGGCUGCUCUCAAACUCCUGGCCUCAAGCCAUUCUCCUGCCUCGGCCUCCCAAAGUGUUAGGAUUAUAGGUGUGAGCUGUCGUGCCCAGCCUAAAAUUCUUACUCUUAAGAAUGGGAAAGCAAGUGCUUCUACUAUUAUGUGAUACAUGUAUUUCUGAAAAGUCUCGUACUUCUACCCACUAAAAAUAAGAAAGCCACAUGGAAAAAUGGGGCUUGGAAUAGACCAGAGAACUAACAAAAAUAAUAACAGUCCUAAUAAAAAUACUAGUUAAAUACCUAGUUAACAAAACAUGUUAAAUUCCUAAUAAACAGAGUAAAUACAGGAUUUCAUCUUAAAAAUGAAGUGAAGGUAGCUUUAUGGCAGGGGUUGUGAAGAAAGGUUAACGAUGCUGAGUAAUUGCAUAAAUGGAUAAAGCUUUGGGAGAAAUGCAUAAAGAUAGAGGGGAACCAUGCAAUGAGCAUUUUCAAGACAGCACACGGCCAGACUGAGAAAAGAGGAAGAACCUGGUUGAAUAGGCAUCAUGUGUGACACGGUUCCCUGUAGCUUUCUGGCCAGUAUACUUUGCAUUCUGUGGCUGUUACUUAGUGAUACAAAGCAUUAAGGAAUUGGGAGCUAUCACCUGUGAAUCAGACUGAUUUCUACUGUUACACUGGCAUCAGGUCUCUAUUGACAAUUUUAUAGAAUCAAAUUCACGUUGCAGAACUAACUUUGCAACAGAUCAUACCAUAGUAACAAUAAUAGCUAUUAAACUUUGUGCCUUGGCACUGCUAAACACUGUACAUAUAUCAUCCUAUUUAGUCUUAACAUAAAGCCACAGGGUGCAAUGGCUCACACCUGUAAUCGCAGCACUUUGGGAGGCUGAGGCAGACGGAUAUCCUGAGCCCAGAAGUUCAAGACCAGACCGGACAAUAUGGUGAAACCUUGUCUCUAUGAAAAUAUUAAAAAGUUAGGCCGGGCGCGGUGCCUCACGCCUGUAAUCCCAGCACUUUGGAAGGCCAAGGCGAGUGGAUCACAAGGUCAGGAGAUCAAGACCACCCUGGCUAACACGGUGAAAUCCCAUCUCUGCUAAAAAUACAAAAAAUUAGCCAGGUGUGGUGGUGGGCGCCUGUACUCCCAGCUACGUGGGAGACUGAGGCAGGAGAAUGGCAUGAACCCAGGAGGUGGAGCUUGCAGUUAGCCGAGAUCCCGCCACUGCACUCCAUCCUGGGCGACAGAGCGAGGCUCUGUCUCAAAAAAAAAAAAAAAAAAAAAGAGUAUUGAUUCACAUGAUCACAAGGUGAAGUCCCACAGUAGGCCAUCUGCAAGCUGAGGAGCAAGGAAGUCAGUCCGAGUCCCAAGUCCUCAAAAGUAGGGAGGCCAACAGUGCAGCCUUCAGUCGGUGGCCAAAGGCCUGAGAGCCCCUGGCAGGCCACUGGUAUAGGUCCAAGAGUCUGAAAGCUGAAAAACUUGGAGUUCGAUGUUCGAGGGCAGGAAGCAUCCAGCACAGGAGAAAGAUGGAGGCCAGAAGACAUAGGCAGUCUAGUCCUUCCAUGUUCCUCUGUACGCUUUUAUCCUAGCUGGGCUGGCAGCUAACUAGAUGGUGCUUUCUCAGAUUGAGGGUGGGUCUGCCUCUCCUAGUCCACUGACUCAAAUGUUAAUCUCGUUUGGCAACACCCUCACAAACACACCCAGGAAUAAUACUUUACAUCCUUCAGUCCAAUCAGGUUGACACUUAAUAUCAACAUCACACUGUCGCCCAGGCUAUAGUACAACGACAGGGUUGUAGCUCACUGCAGCCUCACUCUUGGGCUCAAGCAGUCCUUCCACCUCACCCUUCCAAGUAGCUAGGACUACAGGUGUGCGCCACCAUACCCAGCUAUUUAUUUACUUACUUAGUAUUGUAGAGAUGGGUUCUUGCUAUGUUGCCCAGAGUGGUCUGCAACUCCUGGGCUCAAGCAGUUGUGAGCCACUGUGCCCAUUCUAAAUUUUUAAAUUAGCUUGUUAGGGUUAUACACAUAUGGAAACAAAAACCUGCUGACUGCUGACUUUUCAGAGUUGGAAUUGCAAAUACUUAAAUGAAUCAAUUUAGAGAGAGUUGAUCUCUUCAUCAUAUUGAGUCUUCCGAUCCAUCAUGGAAAAUCUUUCAAUUUAUUUAAGUUUUCUUUGAUUUUUUUUCUGCAAAAAUUAAGCACGUCUUUAUUUCCCAAUGUUUUAUGUUCUAUGAUGCUAUUUAUAAAUAUCUUAUUGAAAUUUUAUUUUCUCUCACUGGUAUAUAGAAAUGUAAAUGAUUUUGUUUAUAGAUUUUUUUAACAAUCUUGCUCUUACGAAUUCUAAUAAAUUCAUUUAGAUUUUUAUGUUAUCUAUGAUUUAAUGACAGUCUUAUCUUUUUCUUUCUAAUCCUUAUGUUUUUGUCUUGACUUAUUCUGGCAGAGAGCUCCAGUACAGUGUUGAAUGGAAGUGUUGAUAGCAGGCAUCCUUGCCUUGUUCCUCAUCUUAAAAGGAAUGAUUUCAACAAUUUGCUAUGAGCCUUUAUUCGAUUAAGGACAUUGGAAUAAAAGUUGUUAUAUUCAGCAAAUACUGAAUUUUAUCAAAUGCUAUUUUUAAAAAUUUUUUUAAUUUUUAAUUUUGUGAAUACAUAGUAGGUGUAUAUAUUUGUAGGGUGCAUGAGAUAUUUUGGUACAAGUAUACAAUGCAUAAUAAUUACAUCAGGGUAAAUGGGAUAUCCAUUACCUCAAGCAUUCAUCAUUUCUUUGUGUUAUGAACAUUCCAGUUGUACUCCCUCAGUUAUACUGAAAUGUACAACUUAUUGCGGACUGUAAUUACGCUGUAGUGCUAUCAAAUAUUAGAUCUUAUUUAUUGUAUCUAACUAUAUUUUGUACCCAUUAACCAUCCCCGCCACUACCCUUCCUAGCCUCGGAUAACCAUCAUUCCAUUCUCUAUCUCCAUGAGUUCGAUUGUCAGAUGCUCUUUUUUUUUAUGAUCUGAGAUGAUCAUAUGAUUUCUCUUUUUUGAUCAGGUAAUGUGAAUUAGCUUGACUUUGUAAUAUUAAACCCAUCUUGUAUUCUGCAGUUAAUCUCAACUUGAUAGGUUAAUCUGGAUUAUACUCUUUAUACACACACACACACACACACACACACACACACAUUCUUAGUUUGCUAACAUUUUGUUUAGGGAUUUUGCAUCUGUGUUCAUGAGUGAGAUUAACUUUUAAUUUUUCUUAAAUUUAUGCUAGCCUCAUAAAAUGAGUUGGGAGAAGGUUCCCUUUUCUCCUCCCUCCUAUAAUAAUGUAUAUAAAAUGAGAAUUAUUUGGUCCUUAAAUGCUUAUAGAACACACCAGUAAAACUGUUGGUGCCUGGAAAAAUUUUUAACUACUGAUAGAAUUUCUUUAAUGGUUAAGACUAUUCGGAUUUUUUAGUUGUGAUUGACUCAGUUUUAAUAAGUUGUACCUUCUUCAAAGAAUUUGUUCAUUUUGUCUGAGUUUUCAAAUUUAUUGGCAUCUAGUUUUUAGAACAUCCUUGUUUUGUAUUUUUUUAUUAUUAUAUUUUUUUAUUUUUGAGAUGGAGUUUCACUCCUGUUGCCAAGGUUGGAGUGCAAUGGCGCGAUCUUGGCUCACUGCAACCUCCACCUCCCGGGUUCAAGCAGUUCUCCUGCCUCAGCCUCCCGAGUAGCUGGGAUUACAGGCAUGAGCCACCACGCCUGGCUAAUUUUGUAUUUUUAGUAGAGAUGGGAUUUCUCCAUGUUGGUCAGGCUGGUCUCGAACUCCCGACCUCAGGUGAUCCACCUGCCUCAGCCUCCCAAAGUGCUGGGAUUACAGGCGUGAGCCACCAUGCCUGGCCUUGUUUUCUAUUUUUAAUGUUUGAAGUAUCUCCAGUUAUAGUCUCCUUUGCAAUCCUAGUAUUAUUUGUCAUCUCUCUUUUUUUCCCUGGUCAUUUUCACCAGAGUUGUUUUAUCACUGAUUAAUUUGUCUUUAUUAUUUUCUUCCUUCUACUUUCUUUGCACCUAUUUUGCUAUUCUUUUUAUAAAUUUUUAGGAUAGAUACUCAGCUUAUUGAUAUCUCAGCCUUUCUUCUUUUCUAAUAUAAGCAUUAGGCUGUAUAUUGUCUUCUGAGUAUAGCUCUAGCCACAUCUAUCCCUAGGCAACCACUGAUCUUCUAAUUGUUUUAGAUGGAUUUGCGUUUUCUAGAAUUUUCUAUUAAAGAAAUCAUGUGUCCACUUUUUUUGUCUUGCUUCUUUCAUUUAGCGAAGUUAUUUGAGACUCAUCCGUAUUGUUGCAUAUAUCAGUAUUUAAUUCCUUUUUACGUUGUAUCCAUUGUAUAGAUAUGCUUAAUCCAUUCACCUGUUGAUGGACAUUUGGGUUACUUCCAGUUUUUGACUAUUACAACUAAAGUUGCUGUGAACAUUUGUGUAUGUCUUUGUGAGAACAUAUGCUUUUCUUUUUCUUGGGUAGAUAGCUAGGAGUGGAAUUGCUGGAUCAUAUGGUGGUUUUUUUUUUUAAAGAGACUGCCAAAUUGUUUUCCAAAGUCAUUGUAUGAGUUCAUAUUCCUGCUUGCAGUGCAGGAGAGUUCUAGUUGCCCUACAUCCUUGCCAACUCUUAAUAUUGUCAGUCUUUUUACUCUUAGGCAUUCUAAUAGAUGUGUACUAGCUCUUAAUUGUAAUUUUAAUUUGCAUUUCUCUGAUGACUAAUAAUGUUGAACAUCUUUUCAUGUGAUUAUUUGCCAUCCAUACAUCAUCUUUGAUGAAGUGUUUUAUCAAAUCUUUUGCCUAUUAUUAAAAUUGAGUUAUUUCUUUUCUUGAGUUUUGGGAGUUCUUUAUAUAUUCUGGAUAAGAUACAUGUCCUGUAUGAGCUAUAUGGUUUGCAAAUGUUUUUCUCCCAAUCUAUGGCUUAUAUUUUCAUUAUCUUGGCAGAGUCUCUUGAAGAAUAGAUUUUUUUAUUUUGAUAGUGGUUGUUUUAAAUUUUUAUGAAUCAUGCUUUUAAUGUCAUAUUUUAAAAUCUUCGCCUAAUCCAAGGUCACAUUUUUCUCCUGUGUUUUCACUAAAAGUUUUAUAGCUCUAGGUUUUACAUCUGUGAUUACCUUUUUGUUACGUUUUAAUUUAAUCACAAUGUAAUCAGAGGAUCUGAUCUUUAUGAUACUGAUUCUUUGAAAUUGGCUUAAUUUAUUUUUAGUUUAUGUUUUCUUCCAGAAUUUUUGUUAAGUAUUUACAUCCAUGUUUAUGUAGCUAUAGAAAUAUAUAGGUUUUUAAAAUUUAAACUAAAUGGAAUCACACUGGUUAUGAUGUUCUGAAAGCUGAUUCUUUUAACUGUCUCAGAUUUAGAGAUACACAUAAUUCCUUUUUACUCUCAUAUUUUAUAGAUUAGAGCUAUAUUUAUUUAGCUACUCCUCUAAGAUGUGCAUUUAAGUUUGCACAUUGAAGUAUUUUCCAAUUAGAUGCACAUUUAAGUUUUUUCCAGAUUUUCUCAAGCAUAAAUAGUACAGUGAUGGACAUCUUUAUAUAUGCCUCCUUGGGCUCAUAUGUGGGAGUAUCUCUGUAGACUAGAAGUAGAAUUUGAAAUUAAAAGCUAUCUGGGUCAAAGUGUGUCUUCUAAGGGUUUUUCUUUUUUUUCCCAACAGUUUUUUAACAGUCACAUAACUUCAUAUGCAAGAAGUAGCACCAUUAACUAGAUCAGUUAUUAAUUCAGCAGGUAUGCAUCGAGUACAUACUGUGAGAACCUUCCUCUUAGGGGUUUCCAAUUCCUUCAGACUCAGUGCCCCCUUUUUAAACAGUAUUUUUUUAAAGACCCUUUUACUGUACCAAGGUGAUACUCAUAGAAAAUAAAAGCAUUCAUAUGCAAAUAACUUACAAAAAUCAAUAUAUAAUAAUAAUUAUAUUCAGGAGAAAUAAAAGGAAAGCAGCCUAUUAUGAAAUAAUGUGUAUUUCAUGUAAAUGCUUAGGAAUAACUACCAAAGAUGAUAUGACAAGUCACAUACUUCUUAAGUAAGUACAUACUUAAAUAAGGGUACUAAGAAGAUACAAUUGUUUUGUAGAUGAAAUGUAGAGUCAGCUGGAAUAAAUGUUAAAUGGAAUUAAUGUUAGAAUAAGUGAGACUAGACUUACUUAUGAUAAAAACGGUUGACAGGAGGAGUUAUUAAGAAGGAGAAAAUUGAGGAAGGAUGAUGUCCUUGCAAAAGAUCCAUACCUUAUGUGGAAGUGUUGUGCCAAAAUGAUUUCUUACGGUAUGUCUUGCCACAGAGUAAUGACAUUCUGUCAUAGAGAACAUCUCCUUUCUUGAAAUCUGUGUCUGAGGUAUACCUUUAGUGUCUGAUACUUUAAAAAAGACCUUGGAAAGCAUAUCCUUUUAUUGGUCACAGAAAAUAGAGAAUUAGAAAAUGAAAGCAUUUUGUCUACCAGAAUAAAAAAUCAAAAAUUAGCAUCUGCUAUGGGAGAAGAUAACAUCUUAUUCAGGGUCACAGGUUGAGCAUUGCACUUGAUUUCUUCAGGGAAAUUGUUAAUAGGAGUGCCACCCAAACGUGAACGUAAUUCUAAGUGUAGUGUGUUUCCAUGUAAUCAGCUGCCCACCAGGAUGAUUCAGGUUAGCUUUGUAAUUGCAGAAGCAGCCUAGUUUUUUUAAAUCUUUAGUAGCAAUUAAUAGGCAAGGAGACUGAUAAUUAUGUUUCACAGUAGACUUUUAUACCUCAUUUUACCAAGAAAAAAAGUUUCUGUGUUAUUUCUUAGAUGGGUAAGAAGAGUUUUUAUUUAUUUUUUAUUUUAUUUGAGGCAGAUUCUCACUCUGCCACCCAGGCUGGAGUCCAGUGGCAGGAACACAGCUCACUGCAAUUUCAAUCUCCUGGGCUCAAGCAAUCCUCCCACCUCAGCCUCCCAAGUAGCUGGGACUGCAGGCACAUGCCACCACACCCAGCUGGUUUUUUUAUUUUUUGUAGAGAUGAGGUCUCUCUGUGUUACCCAGGAUGGUCUUGAACUCCGGGGCGUAAGCAAUCCUUCCGCCUUGGCCUCGCAGAGUGCUGGGAUUAGAGGUAUGAGCCACCAUGCCCUGCCAAGUUUUUCUUUUAAAAGUGAAGAAAAAUAUGAAGAACACCAGUAAUUUCAGAUGUGGGGUAGAAAAUAAGAUCAUUCAUACUGCUAAUUUCUAGCAAUAUUUGCUGGUUUUAAAAGGUAGCCUUGUAUUUGAAAGUUUUUUUUAAUUAUAAAAGUUGUUAAUUUCUUUAUUACCACACUAUGUAAAAAUAGUCAUUUCCACCUCUACCUCUGUCACUUCUUAAUCUCCUUACUCGUACUUGUCUUCCUCCAUAAUGCUUCUCAUUAUCUACAAACAUAUAUACUUAAUUUGUUUAUCACAUUAGAAUGUAGAUUCCAGGAAGACCAGAACUUUAUUUCAUUUGCUGUUGUGUUCCCAGUGCCUGAAAUACAGUGCCUGGAACACAGUGAGCAAUCAAGAUACGUUUAUUGAAUGAAUAAAUCUUUUGCUCUUUUCUCACGUGCAUAUCAUCUGGUUGUAAUCACAGUGUGCAUAUAACUUUGUGUCUUGUGUUUUUAUAAAAUGUUAUUACACAGAAUAAAUAUCAUCUUUUCCCCAGGUUGCCACAUAACCUGCUUUGAUCAUUAUUUUUCUGUAUCCCGGAAACAUAGCAUAAUUUACUAACCCGUCUCCUAGUUUGGGACAUAUAAAUUGCUUUUGAUCUUUCUGUAUUAUAAAUUAAUAGUAUAUUCAUGUGAGGAUGAAAAGAUGCACAGAUGGACAGACAGAUGUAUAUAUAGACAGACAGGUAAACUUUACAGUGGAAGAACUGGAGAAGUAGCUCUGCAGCUUGGAACAACACCCAGAAUCACACUGCAGAGCCAGUCUCGUGAAGCUAUGGCUGUACAGCCAGUACCACAAAGCUUGGAGAUGGACCUCCAGCUUCCAGUGCCAAGUCUCUCAGACCAGUGAAUCUUAUUGACCCCCUGCUCUCCUCCAAGGGAAGCAGGACUGCAAAUAUCUGGUAUUGUCUGUUUUUACAGGUAGAGAGAGGCACUGCCUCACCCAAACCACUGGGAGAAGGAAUUCUUAUAUUUCCUAGAAAAAUAAUUUAGGACCACACACUGAUAAAGCCAUUUCUAUAUUUAGGAUAAUUUAUAUAACGUGGGUUCCCAGAAGUAUAAUUAUCAGGCCAGAGGGCAGGAGCAAAUUCUGAUGAUGAAGGACCAGAUCUCUUGACCUCAAUGGUUUAGUCUUGGAACUUUUUGCUUCCUUUAUUAAUCUUUCCUUUUACACAUACGUAAAGCACAUUUAUUGGCUGUACUUAUUCACUUAGUGAAUAGAGUGUUUUGUUUCUUAGAACUUUAAAUAGUUGUUGAGGUGAAGGGACUUAUAGUCAAAGGAGAAUCAUCAUCUCUUUUUUUUCCCCUCUUGAUUAAUUUUUUUUCUCUUUUAGAUAGCGGUGCCUGGGUUUGUGCUAGAAUCUGAAAAUGGAUGACAUAUUCAUCCAUUCAUCACAUAUGGUGAAUUUAUUUCACCAUAAAUUGUUUUAUGUUAGUGCACAUGCAAACUUCUGUUUGUAUGUGUGGAGUGGAAAUUUCAUCAUUUAUAGCAGUGUGAAUUUAUUCUCAAAUGUUUUCUUUCAGCCUCCUUCUCCACCCUAUGUAAAAGUAAAUAUCCGUAAUACCUCUUUUCUCCUACUCUUCCCCUAGGCUUUUGUUUUGUUUUUGCUGAUUGGUCAGCAUUCACUUCAUAUCAGUUGUUGAGGUAUAAAAACCAAGUAAUGAGUCCCCAUGUCCAUCAGGGGGCUACAGCCUGCCUUAGUGGCAGGUGCUCUUGUCUCAAAGCCAGAGAACCUAGGUGUUAGUUUCAGCCUCACCACUAAUGCACUGUGACUUCAGGAGCUCCCUCCCCUCAGUGGCUUUGGGGAAGGGGUGGGACUUAGAGUUGAAGUCAUUCUGUGGACCUAUUACAGUGUUCUUCAUUUGCUCUGACUACAUUUGCGUAUCUUCCUGCCAGAAUGGGAGGCUUCUGAGUCCAGAACUCAAUCUUGUAUUCAUGUGCCCGGUGCGUGUUGGGUGGAUAUGGUUAAAUGAGCCCAGUUUUGUUGUUCUUGUGGGUCUUUUCUAUGUAACACAGUCCAUAUAUUCUUGCCUACACUUUAAGUGAAAGAGGAACUUGUAAAGACCUCCUAUCUUUAAGAAUAUUAGGGCCAGGCAUGGUAGCUCACACCUGUAAUUCCAGUGCUUUGAGAGGCCCAGGUGGAAGGAUCACAUGAGUUCAGGUAUCAGUCUGGGCAACAUAGUAAGACCCUGUGUCUACAAAAACUAAAUUAAAGAAAAAAUUUGACUGGGUGUGGUGGCUCACGACCUGUAAUCCCAACGCUUUGGGAAGCUGAGGGAGGCAGAUCACAUGAGGUCAGGAGCUUGAGACCAGCCUGGCCAACAUGGUGAAACCCCAUCUCUACUAAAAAUACAAAAUUAGCAGGGUGUGGUGGCAGGCACCUGUAAUCCCAGCUACUCGAGAGGUGGAGAUAAGAGAAUCGCUUGAACCUGGGAGAUGGAGGUUGCAGUGAGCCGAGAUUGCACUCCAGCCUGGGCGACAAGAGCAAGACUCCAUCUCAAAAAAAAAAAAAAAAAAAAAAAAAAAAAUUACUGGGUGUGGUGGCACAUACCUGUAGUCCUGGCUACUCUGAGAGGCUGAGGCAGGAGGAUCACUUGAGCCCAGGAGGUCAAGGCUGCAGUGAGCCAUGAUUGCACCACUGGCACUGCAGCCUGAGUGACAGAGCCAGACCUUGUCUUUAUUUAAUAAAAAGAAGAAUAUUAGAUUACUGCACCGUUAGGUUGAAGAUGCUAUAUGCAGAACAUGGUGUUUCUGGGCUCUCCAGGUCUUUCCUCCUCUCCUUGUAGGUUUAAAAAUGUUUUGAGUUGGUUGGACUCCAUGGUAACAUUCUUGUGAACUUUCAGUUGAGGAAAGGUGAUCUUUAAGGGGAAAGGGGUGGAGGGAGAGAGAGUUUAACAGUGGCAGCAAUCUAGGUGAAGGGAGAACUUUGUAAAGCAGAGUACAUCUUCCCUAGAAGCAAUUAGUCAUAUUAUUAGACAAACUGUUUCAGCAGCUGGCAAAACAGCAGGAACAUGUCGAUUUUGCUUCCUUGGUUACAGGCAGUGAUAGUGUACUUGACCUUCCGCAGAGCUGGGUCACAGAGAGGGCAUCUUUAAACAGCCCUGUCUGGUUUGGGUGAAUGGAAUCUGCACUGGCAGGGUUUGAAAGCAAAUGCCUGUGAGUUCCCUCAACCAACCUCUGGCCUUUUGGGUUGGACUCUCUUUGGCCUGGGAGGUUGCUGAGGAAAAAUAUAAAUAAAGCUGCAGGGAGCCAUUGGCAUGGUAACACGUACACAGACCUCUCGGCCGGAAUCUCCAGGGAUGACCAGCCCCUCCCCACGCAUCCAGAUAAUCUCCACCGACUCUGCUGUAGCCUCACCUCAGCGCAUUCAGGGCUCUGAACCUGCCUCUGGCCCAUUGAGUGUUUUCACAUCUUUGAACAAAGAGAAGAUUGUCACAGACCAGCAGACAGGACAGAAAAUCCAGAUAGUCACCGCAGUGGACGCCUCCGGAUCCCCCAAACAGCAGUUCAUCCUGACCAGCCCAGAUGGAGCUGGAACUGGGAAGGUGAUCCUGGCUUCCCCAGAGACAUCCAGCGCCAAGCAACUCAUAUUCACCACCUCAGACAACCUCGUCCCUGGCAGGAUCCAGAUUGUCACGGAUUCUGCCUCUGUGGAGCGUUUACUGGGGAAGACGGACGUCCAGCGGCCCCAGGUGGUAGAGUACUGUGUGGUCUGUGGCGACAAAGCCUCCGGCCGUCACUAUGGGGCUGUCAGUUGUGAAGGUUGCAAAGGUUUCUUCAAAAGGAGUGUGAGGAAAAAUUUGACCUACAGCUGCCGGAGCAACCAAGACUGCAUCAUCAAUAAACAUCACCGGAACCGCUGUCAGUUUUGCCGGCUGAAAAAAUGCUUAGAGAUGGGCAUGAAAAUGGAAUCUGUGCAGAGUGAACGGAAGCCCUUCGAUGUGCAACGGGAGAAACCAAGCAAUUGUGCUGCUUCAACUGAGAAAAUCUAUAUCCGGAAAGACCUGAGAAGUCCCCUGAUAGCUACUCCCACGUUUGUGGCAGACAAAGAUGGAGCAAGACAAACAGGUCUUCUUGAUCCAGGGAUGCUUGUGAACAUCCAGCAGCCUUUGAUACGUGAGGAUGGUACAGUUCUCCUGGCCACGGAUUCUAAGGCUGAAACAAGCCAGGGAGCUCUGGGCACACUGGCAAAUGUAGUGACCUCCCUUGCCAACCUAAGUGAAUCUUUGAACAACGGUGACACUUCAGAAAUCCAGCCAGAGGACCAGUCUGCAAGUGAGAUAACUCGGGCAUUUGAUACCUUAGCUAAAGCACUUAAUACCACAGACAGCUCCUCUUCUCCAAGCUUGGCAGAUGGGAUAGACACCAGUGGAGGAGGGAGCAUCCACGUCAUCAGCAGAGACCAGUCGACACCCAUCAUUGAGGUUGAAGGCCCCCUCCUUUCAGACACACACGUCACAUUUAAGCUAACAAUGCCCAGUCCAAUGCCAGAGUACCUCAACGUGCACUACAUCUGUGAGUCUGCAUCCCGUCUGCUUUUCCUCUCAAUGCACUGGGCUCGGUCAAUCCCAGCCUUUCAGGCACUUGGGCAGGACUGCAACACCAGCCUUGUGCGGGCCUGCUGGAAUGAGCUCUUCACCCUCGGCCUGGCCCAGUGUGCCCAGGUCAUGAGUCUCUCCACCAUCCUGGCUGCCAUUGUCAACCACCUGCAGAACAGCAUCCAGGAAGAUAAACUUUCUGGUGACCGGAUAAAGCAAGUCAUGGAGCACAUCUGGAAGCUGCAGGAGUUCUGUAACAGCAUGGCGAAGCUGGAUAUAGAUGGCUAUGAGUAUGCAUACCUUAAAGCUAUAGUUCUCUUUAGCCCCGAUCAUCCAGGUUUGACCAGCACAAGCCAGAUUGAAAAAUUCCAAGAAAAGGCACAGAUGGAGUUGCAGGACUAUGUUCAGAAAACCUACUCAGAAGACACCUACCGAUUGGCCCGGAUCCUCGUUCGCCUGCCGGCACUCAGGCUGAUGAGCUCCAACAUAACAGAAGAACUUUUUUUUACUGGUCUCAUUGGCAAUGUUUCGAUAGACAGCAUAAUCCCCUACAUCCUCAAGAUGGAGACAGCAGAGUAUAAUGGCCAGAUCACCGGAGCCAGUCUAUAGCGCAAACCACACACCUGCCAAGGAGCAACAGAAUCCUUCCAGGACCGUUCACAUACAAAGAAAAGUAGUGGUAUUUUGGUAUGUGCAAAUAUUUCCAUAUGUUAGCCAUUUCCUGUCUGGUUUCUCCUUAUCUGUUAAUCCCAGACAAUAGCAAUUAAAAGACUAGUAGGAUCCUUUCCUGACAUAAGAAAUGUUUUAAUGCCUUUUGAUGAAGCAGCAGAUUUUGGAACAAUCUUUUAACUCAAUUUGUAUUUAGAAAUUCUCAAAGGGCAAAAAACAAAAAAAAAGGUUUUAUAAUGUCAGAGACUAGUAUUAAAGAAAACUGAAAGAACCUGAGAGAAUAGUAUGUGUGUAUAUAUAUAUAUAAAAAAGUCCUUGGAAUUAUAGAUACUAAUUACCAGGGUAAUAAUAUUAGCACUUUCUAAGCACUUAUCAAUGUGUAACGUUAGCAACAUCUUGCCUGUGGGCAGGGCAAAUGGAAAACUGUGUAUGUCUUUUGCCGAAAUGCUAAUGAUUUCUGUGAAAACUCACUAGGGUACAGGAGACAAUCAUUUAUGUUUAAGAAAAGAAGGCAUCAUUCCUAAUUGUGUGCACAUGUUGUGGAGUUGAGCUGAAUUCUGUGAAUGGAAACGUGGCUCAUUUGCAUCAUGCAGUAAGUGGGAGUGUGGUAGCACAGUCGGUGGUGACCCAGUUCAGAAGCUUCUAGCCAUAGAGCAGACACUUGUCAGGUUCCCUGACUACUUGGUCCUGGUCUCUGAUGGGCAUCUGCAGACUCCUCUAGAACCUGGGGUUCUCCUUUGAUGACUGGUUAUCUGAAUUGGAUUGCAACUAGUCAGACAUUAACUGCCAAAUGAGAUGUACAGUUCCUCCAGCAAGUGAAAACAUCCCCAAGUCACAUCCGCCGCUCGUGGCAGAUGGAGCCUUGUGACCAAAAAGUGCAAGGUGGGCAUUUUGAGCUCUUGACAGUACUUCCAAUACAAUUGGGGGUGCUUGUGUGUUUGUCCAGAUGGAGGAGUGUGGCCUUGGAGUGUGAGCGUUACCUUCCCAGGGCUUUCCACUCCAAAUGCCCCCUUGAAAAGGGCUCGUGUUUCUGCAGCUCCAUCAUAACUGUGAGGCUGGAUUGGGGCUGGGCAGGAGCCUGCUGCCGCCUGGCGAGAGUGGUUAGGGCCUGGUAAAGCUGGAUGGAAGGUUUCAGGACAAUUUCUUCCUGUUGACCUUAAAUACCAGAGAUUUUAAAAAUGUGUAUAGACUCAGCAUCUCUGUUGGCAAGUCUGUUAAUGUUACCAGCACACUGUGCACUUUGGUUCCCCCAGGUGUGUGCCAGCCGACCACCCCGGAGCAUUUUAAAUGCAGGCUGCUUGCUCCUUAAAAACAACCCUCAAUUUCCAGGGUGAUAGUCUUUCUCCUCAUAAAUUGUAGCAACCAGAGUUUACAGCAAGAACAGUAUGCGCUUAAAAGGAAGUUAUGUCUAACUUCAAACACCCGUAAAUUCCCACGGAUGUGAAUAUAUAGCAAGCUUUUCCUGUUUGAGAACAGUGGCAUGUGGAAGACCCGGUCAAUUGCUUUGUCUUUUGCUUUUUAAAUAGUCCAGAUUAAGAAAAUACACCCUGUUGGGUUAAAUUUGCCUCUCUUGAUUUGUUAAUCAGAUGAUAUCCAAAAAGAUCCCUGGACACUCCCCUGACUCACAGGUGCUCUGAUCUGGCUCAGGCUGGCGCCACAUGUGCUCCACAGGGGUGCAGUCUGGCCAGCUACAGACGCCCCUGUGGUGCCACAUUGGACAGAAUGGAAGCUGCUGCAGGCUCAAGGCAGAACAGGAUGCUUGAUCCUGAAGGGUUAGCAGCACUUUACGCAAGUCAGUGUUAGUAGGGUAAGUGGGAACAGUGUUUCCAACUUCUAAAUUCUUGUUUGGAUUUAAUUAUAUCAUUUUAUAAUUCUUGCCUUGGCAGCAAAUUUUGGAGAGUAGUGGGAGUGGCCAUUAUAAAAUGAUGGAAAGGAUUUAAUUUUGCCAGCUUAAAGUAAUUUUUACUUUUCUAACCCUGAUGUGUUUUCAGUUUCAAAAUUAAGACAAAAAACCAGCUGAGACAAUGGAAUUAGGGCAGGUUUGUUUCAUUUCUGCUUGUGAAGGCUUUUAGUAGCAGGCAUCCUGCAGCUCAGUGGUGCCUCUAACACAGAUUGUUGCCUGCCUUCCGUCGUUUUGAUCCUUGAGAGUGACCAUGAGGGCCAUGUUGCAGUUCCCUGGGAAUACAAGCAUAACAGCUUUCAGAUCCCAGUUCUUGGUGUUGGUGAAAAGGUCUCCACCAGCCCCUCCUCUCAUUCCCAGGUCAUUCAGUGGCAGCCAGUAGGCUGCUUAGACUCAGGCUGGAUAAGGAAGUGUUGGGCUGUGGUGAAACAACCUUGCAGAAAACGUGAUUUUGCUUGGAAAGGUGCUGAUUCUAACCUGGUCCUGCUCUUUAAGUCCCCUUGCUGGUGAUGGCUGAUUCCAGGGACUGUUUUGGGCUUUGAACACCUCUUGGUUGGUUUCUGAGAUCCUCUUGGCCUUACUUUGAAGUGGCCUUUUCUUUAAGGAUCAUGUCCACGUAACCUGUAUUCUUGCUGCUUUAACUCAUUUCAAGCCUCUGACUGCAGGUCCAUUUCAUCUCCUGUCAGGUUGGUUAAGUAAAGUCAGCCCAAAGUCAAGAAUUACUUAAAGAGAUGCAAACCAAAUAUUUGGGCUCCAACUUUCACAGGGCUUAUAGCCCUUAUUAGCAGUUUGUGAAACUUUGGGUUUCAUGAAGUGAGACCUGUCCUCUGGCUACUGAACUCCAUGGAGCCACGUUCAUGCUCCCUCUUCUACUGGCCUGGCUGCUCCUCCCUCAAUGAGGAGAGGCAGCUGGCUCAGAGAGGUGGGACAGACACAUGCUGUCAUCAGUUAAGUGAGCUCUUUUCCAGAAGUAUCUCAGAUAAUGUUGGGUUAAGACAGAUAGAUGUUGAAAAUGGUGGAGAUCAUUACACAUUAGCAUAAAACAGGACAGGAAGAGAUUUUUUGAAAGACCAAAUUAGUUGAGCAAGUAAUACUUUUCAAGUUACUCCUGGAAGGUGUUUUUAAGGAAGUGUGUUACCUACCAUACUCUCCUAAUUUGACAUUUCUGUGUCCUGAGGAGUUACAUUUAUUGUCUAACCCUUGCCAUAAGGCUGUGGUUUGAGGUUCUUUUGCUGUUCUGGGCUUUAUAUUUAAUUUCAGGUGUAGUCACUUCUAAGAUGUGUAAUUGCCCUCAAGAGGGACUGAUUUUUAGCUUGUCAUUGUCAGUAUUGAAUGUGGACUCUUCUGAGGCAGUUAGGACACCAGCCAUGGUGUUAACAGUGGAUGCGUUAGGCUCCUUAAUCUCAAGGCAAUAUCCACGCUACACACAUACUUAUUAGCUGUCUUACUUGUUUGGGGGAUAGUUACGGCAAGGAGCAAAAAAUUCUAAGGACUCUAGCUGUUUCUAGUGCUUUUACUUUCAUAGUCCUUUGAGGACAUUUCCUGCAGAGCACUCUUGCUCACAGCCCGCCCUCUGCAGGGCUUCCAGCCCCUGGCCGCAAUCAGCAGUUCAUGCCACAUGUGUACAUCCAUGUUCUGGGACCUGAUCUCAUUGGAGUCCAGAAGCUUGUUGCCCACUUUCCAGUGUAAAUGACUUUAUGUGCAAUGGGGUCAUAGGUAACAUUUUAACUCUUUUCUUAGUCCAGGUCAUAGGAAGUCUCAUCAUCUGACAGCCACUUUUCUCCCAGGGAAGGCGGUGCCCACUGGGCCCUGGGAAUGCCUGAGCCAGCAGAGCAGAUGCCCCACGUGCUUCCUUUAUCCAGCUUCCAUUCUCUCAGUUAUGAGGCUCUUUGAAAAUGUCUUAACUUUGAUGUAAAUUUUUAAAGCCAACCCCUCAUCAAGACAGGGUUGGUUUGGGUCUUUUGUACACAGGGUCUGGACCUUCUCAUUGUGUGCCUCCCACCAGCGUGCACUUCGUAUGUCCAGCCCUGGGUCCCUUCAGCAGCAUUGUGCGUGUACAGGUUUCUAGGCUGUAAGACUGAAUGAAUGUACAUGUGUUUAUAUCCUCUCCAUAUGUACAGUGUAUAUAGUGUGUGUAUGUGUACAUAGAUGUAUAUUAUGUAUACAGACAUGUAUCCAAACUUUCCUUUAAAGAGAGUUUUUCAUAAAGUUGCUAAUGUAAACUGAUAUGGGUGUUCCAAGGUCCCUCGGCAGGGAAGAUUUGCUGGUGAUUUUCUUCACUCCAUUUUCCUUUGGGUGAGCCUGCCUGGGAAGGGCCAUGAAGUCAGAAUCUCCACUCUGCAAAAGGAAGAAUUCCAGGCAGAAGAGGUUCUGACAGGGUGACAUUUCCGUAUAUUCUCUAGGUUCGGACAAGAGCCAGGAAGCUGGAAGACAGUUUAUCUUAAUAUCCAAAACUAAGUGGGAAUUUUUAACCUUUUCAUGCACCUAUUCAUGGCCCUACCUGGAAGGAACUUGGCAGUUGGGUUGAGCCAUCAGCCUUCCCAGCUAUUCAGCUCUGUUGAGUAGCCCAGAGACAGGCGUCACGGUCAGAGAUUCAGAACGGUCUGUGUCAGUGAGGCCUGACUCCCAAAGAUGGUAGCAAUUUCCCAGGCUUGCGCUGUGCUCAGUCAGCAAGAUGUGGGGCACUGUCCUAUGACUGAAUAAAUAGUAAUUCCCAUCUUUCUAUCGCCAGUUAAAAAUAAACAACCUACCAAGUAUUAUUCUUUAAAACUAAGCAUGGAUGUUGAUGGCUAACUUCUGCGGCAUAUAAGCUACAGAUCUCAAGUUACUUCUCUAACUGUAAGCAUGUAAAUGACUUUAACUCCUUUCUAUAAGUUAUGAUUUUAAAUUUUCAGAUAAGAAUUGCAUUUUAAUAUGGAUAUGUGUGCCCUUAAAAGCUACAGAUACCAAAUUUUCCUCGUCCAGGUCUACUCGGACGAAUUUUCCCCCUUAAUCUGGCCUUAAACUGAGACUCGGCCCUUGAGAGCCAGGGCCUGGCCCAGCAGUAGUUGCUCAUAGACCUGGGAAGCAGGGGCCUGCUGGAAGGAAUCACUAGAUUGCUGCAAAAACUCACAUAAUCCACAGUUUCCUCUUUUUCUUUUUAAAAUAAGUUAUCAAAAUGUUUUAAAAACACUUUAUGAGACCAUAGUACUCAGUGCCUUUUGUGAGACAGUGGGUCAUUUAGCCUUCAGCUUCCCUGUUUUUGAUGUAGAGAAAGCUUCUAUUUCACUGGCCUCAUCCCACAAGAUUGUGCGACCUUUCCCCGUCAUAGCCUGUCGUGACAAUCACGCUAUUGAAAGUGGCUUUCUAGUUAAAAUGCAAUUGGAAACUUGACAGUCUCUAAAUGAAUUAAAAGUUUCCUUUGGGGCUAUUUAGCUUAACAGCAGUCUACAAAUAAUUAAAGUGUGAGCUUAAGAAAAGUAUCUUUGCGGGGAGAAAAAUGUCAGAUAUUUUUAAUGCCCAGCUAUAAAUAAUUUUGGUGUCUUGAUAUUUAUACAUGCAAAAUAGAAAAAAAAUGUUCAACAUUUAUUGAUUGAUAGACUGUUAAAAUUUAAUGUUUGGAAUAACAUUUGGAAGUAGUAGACUUUGCAUUAAAAAAUGGCUUUUCUUUAGGAAAGUAUAAUCAAUUAUUUUAAUGACCAUAGCAUUCAUGGACUCAAAUGCUGCUGCCACACACAACUCAAGUGCUGGAAUAUUUUUCUACAGUCUCUCUGUUCUACGGAUUAUCUUGUAAACCAGUGUUCAACUAGUUUUAUAACUGAAAAGCUGCACAUUUUUCACAGUACAAGCCGUAGUUUUUACCUGUAGUUUGGACUUCUCUGUUAGAAUGUAACUGCAUUACCAGCCCUUUUAAAGGCAUCUAUCUAUCAAAGGAAAAUUUGGGUGUUAGAUUUUCUUGGGACCGUUUCUGUAACCUUUGCCCUUCACAAUAUAGAAAAUAUUGGUUUUGCCAUUACAUUUUAAUGCCAGGUUUAAAACCUGUUGAAAGCUGCAGCUUUAUACAGCUUUCUUCUCCCUGUGAAAUCACUUUGUUUAUGUGAUGGCAUUUAAAAAAUAGCAUGUUCUUUUUAAACUGAAUUUUAUAUCUAAUCAAUGUCUUCAGUCUUGAAGAAGAAUUUGCAUUGUUGUGUUUGUAUAUAGAGUAUUGCAGUGCAUGAAUUAGCUUUAUGCAUUUUAUUAAAUGCUGUUUCAAUGUGGCAUUAUUGUUGUGGCUUAAUACUACUACCUAAAUGAGGUUUAUACUAUUAAAAGUGAAUUAAAGACUAA